AGUUCCGGGGGCCAGGCGGCCGCCGCGAGUCUGGUAUCCUGAGCUUCGUGAGUUGAGCGCUGCUGCUCCGCGGUGGAGUCACCGCACCGCUCCCGGGAUCAUGGUGUUCUACUUCACCAGCAGCAGCGUUAAUUCAUCUGCCUACACUAUUUACAUGGGAAAAGAUAAAUAUGAAAAUGAAGAUCUGAUCAAGCAUGGCUGGCCUGAAGAUAUCUGGUUUCAUGUGGACAAACUCUCUUCGGCUCAUGUAUACCUUCGAUUACAUAAGGGAGAGAAUAUAGAAGACAUCCCAAAGGAAGUGCUGAUGGACUGUGCCCACCUUGUGAAGGCCAAUAGCAUUCAAGGCUGCAAGAUGAACAACGUUAAUGUGGUAUAUACGCCGUGGUCUAACCUGAAGAAAACAGCUGACAUGGAUGUGGGGCAGAUAGGCUUUCACAGGCAGAAGGAUGUAAAAAUUGUGACAGUGGAGAAGAAAGUAAAUGAGAUCCUGAACCGAUUAGAAAAGACCAAAGUCGAGCGGUUCCCAGACCUAGCAGCAGAGAAAGAAUGCAGAGAUCGUGAAGAGAGGAAUGAGAAAAAAGCCCAAAUUCAGGAAAUGAAAAAGAGAGAAAAAGAAGAAAUGAAGAAGAAGAGGGAAAUGGAUGAACUUAGGAGCUAUUCAUCACUAAUGAAAGUUGAAAAUAUGUCUUCAAAUCAGGAUGGCAAUGAUUCAGAUGAAUUCAUGUAAAAGGAGAAAAGGAGAAAAGGACCUUUGAAAGAUGUGAAUGUAGAGACAAUUGCAGACCUUUUGGUUUCAUCUGUGUUCUGAAAUAUAAAAUACAACCAAAAUUCUACCUUCAUCCUACCCAGAAAUUAUUGAUUUUCAAGUUUUAAAAAAAUUGUACCUUUUUUGCUGACAGAAAAGGAUCAGAUAUGUAUAAAAUAGUUGAACUUGACAGCAUAUAACUUAAAGUGAAAAUGUUUUUGCCAGAACAUGUCUUGGUACCUUGUGAAAGCAGGCUGCCCUUGUUCUUGAGAUAGACUUUAAAAUGAACCAGCUCUGAAAAGUACUUCUGCUGCUCUGGUCUAUCCCUGAAAACAGAUGUCUUGAAACACUUUUCAUAUUCUUAAAAUAAUCUUCACUUCUGUUAAGAAGAACAUGUUGGUGGGUAAUUAUGCGAAUGUUUCCCUGUCCCUGAUUUCUCGAUUAGGCGUAUGGGUUUUGAAAAAGAGAUUUUUCAGAAGAUUGUCAGCUUCAGUAUUCAUGUUCCAUCGUGUCAUCUGGGUCUGUUAGUGUAGUGACCCUCAGUGCAGUCUGUCCCAGCGUUUACGUCCUUGCUUCCUCUGAGCAGAGGCCUCCAUCUUAGUAUCAACAUAUUUAAAGAAAUUGAUGGUGUUCAUCAAGCUGGGGCCUGUGGCAGUUGUUGCCUGAGCACCAAGUAACCCAAGCCACCUAUGUGACAACUUCUGGGCCCAGGAGUAAUUUCUCAGCAUUGAGGGUAAAAUAGGAUGGAGUGCUCUGUUGAUCAUUUGGGAGAUGUAGGUUACCUGAUUUGUGCCUUAGGAUGCAGCGUGAAGCAGAAGUCCAUAUUGCAAUUAUGAUUUUAGAAGGAACUAAGCAUUUUACUCACACCCACAGCAGCAAGAAUGACCUCCUGCAGCAGAUAUUCCACCUGUAAUAGCACUUUGGAACUGUGGGCAAAACCAAAAGGCUAGUGUUUCCAUUUAUUCCAUGUUGGUGUAUGGGGUUGAACUGGAAAAUUCCCUGAGGCAAAACUCACUGGCCAAAUUUUGAGAGGGUAUAGAAAAUGACUUUAGAGAUGAGUGGUUUUGUGUAUGUGUCUGAUGAUAUUCAGUCUGAUGUUCCGCAAUUUUAAAAGUUAUAAUAAAAUACCAUUUUUUUAAUCUGGAAGGACAUUGAUAUAUGAAUUCUUAGAAUUUGCUAUUAAAAAGGGUAGCCCCCAUUCCACAAGCUGGUUUUGAGGGUGAUCUUGCUCUAAAAAACCUCAUUCAUCAUAGGCUCAGUCUGACAGGUUCUGUACGGGGCUAUCAUCUUUCUCCUCCUCUGCUAAAUGCCUCUUUCUUCCAGCUGCUCACUGGGUCAAAGGGAUGUCCUUUCUCAGAUGUAUUCUUGAUACAUCUCAGAUGUAUUCGUAGCUGUGCUCCUUCCAUACUUCCAAGGAGUCCGGCUUCUACAGAAUUCCUCUGUACCUCACACUGCAACACAUGUAGAUAGCGCUUUUGAAAAAUACAUAUAUUUUUACUAUAGUAUGAGAGGUCCUGGGGCUCAAACUUUAAACAUUUCCUAACUCAGCUUACACUGGUUUAAAAUGUCCAGGUCUCUGCUGAAUUCUCUUGUUGAAUUCAUAGCUCUGUGUUGAUUCCUAUGCCCCUAACCCUGCAGCCUCUUUGUUUUAUUUUUUUCCCCAUCUCUGUUGGUCCCAGGGAAAGCAAGGAAAUUUUCUUUUGAGGACUUAUAGGUUGAUUGCCCACAGGUCAAACUGUUGGCAUUGAACUCCUCUCAUUUCUUGCCAUUGGAUUGUUUCCUAAACGUUGGAUAGGAGAAUUCGAAAUUGUUGCUAUUUUUAUGAGCUGUGCCCUUGAUCAAAUCUGUGCUGUGGGUCUGAGUCACUUUGCCAAUGUCGUCUUCAGUUUCAACACUCUGAUCAGCAUGCAGGCGAGGGGCAUGUUUAAUUUACUUCACUAACUGCUAUAUUCUAUAGCUUUAGACUUCAUAUUUCUUAUCCACCUUUGUCUAGGCUCACGAUCUUUGGGCAAGGGAGCUUUGUCACCGUGGUUGGGCUAGAACAAAUAUUGAGAAGUUUACCAACACAGAUGUUGAGAAGUUUAUUGAAAGGCACUGACAUUAGCAGAAUAAGUGAUGGACAUUAGUUGAACCCCUUCAGUGUCUAUGUGUUUUAUUGUAUUGUCUUUAACUCGUUCUUGAAGCACAGAUUUCAGCGAGCCUUUCAGCUAUUCAGUGCCAGCGGUUUUCCCCACUCAGGAAAGAUGGUGUGAGCCAUACACACAGCAGGAUUAGACGGGGAGAGUUUCAGCUGCAGCUUCUAGUUUAAGACCAAAGCCCUUCCUCCCGCUGCUGCAUCUGUCUGAGAGGGGAAGCUCUUGUUUUCCAAGCUGGAACCGUUUAUGAGGAAAACUGAGCAGGGUGGCAAAAUGGAAAAGGAACAAUUUUCUAGUUUUUCCUACGCGUGAUAUUGACGCGUGCUUUUUCUUUGAUUUGAGGUACAGCAUGUAAAUAACAAAUUUCCAUAUUCAAAAUGAUCAUAUUAGAGUGACUGAGUGACCUUUUGAUUUUGAAGCAGACUAAAAUCUGACCAGACCACAAUGAAAAGUAUAAAAUUAGAAACUUAAAUUCCAAGCUAAAUUUCAGCUUUGACCCACCUAACUCCAGUGAAUAGGUGGCAGCUCAGAAACAAGGACAGCACUGCUGCUGCCAGAGCAAGCUCACAUCCAGCUGGCACUUCGUGAGAGCUCCUUCCUGCCGGGCACGUGUGAGUUCAGCGUGGGCAAGAGACUUUUAUGCACAUUCUGUCAUUCAAAAGGGAAAUGAUGCCAACCCCAGAUGCAGCAUGUCCUGAAUGAAUGAUCUGUAAAAUACAAUAAUAAAAGCUUAUAGUUUGAGUAGAA